GGAAAAAAGGAAAGUGCACUUGGAAGAGAUCCAAGUGGGCAACUUGAAGAACAAGUGCCGAAUAGCACUUCUGUCAUGCUGGAUGUCAGGGCUCUUUGUCCACUUUGUAUAGCCGCUGGCUUAUAGAAGGUGCUCGAUAAAUCUCUUGAAUUUAAAAAUCAAUUAGGAUGCCUCUAUAGUGAAAAAGAUACAGUAAAGAUGAGGGAUAAUCAAUUUAAAAAAUGAGGAGUAAGUACACACAAAGCACUUUAUCCAUUCUUAUGACACCUGUUACUUUUUUGCUGUGUUUGUGUGUAUGCAUGCCAUGUUAUAGUUUGUGGGACCCUCAAAGCAAGCUGGGGAGAGUAUAUACUGAAUUUAGCUUCUGAGACAUGAUGCUCUUCCUUUUUAAUUAACCCAGAACUUAGCAGCUUAUCUAUUUCUCUAAUCUCAAAACAUCCUUAAACUGGGGGUGAUACUUGAGUGAGAGAAUUUUGCAGGUAUUAAAUGAACUAUCUUCUUUUUUUUUUUCUUUGAGACAGAGUCUUGCUCUGUCACCCAGGCUGGAGUGCAGUGGCGUGAUCUCAGCUCACUGCAACCUCCGCCUCCCGGGUUCAAGUGAUUCUCCUGCCUCAGCCUCCUGAGUAGCUGGGAUUACAGGUGCGUGCCACCGUGCCCAGCUAAUUUUUGUGUUUUUAGUAGAGACGGGGUUUCACCAUGUUGGCCAUGCUGGUCUUGAACUCCUGACCUCGUGAUCUGCCCACCUCGGCCUCCCAAAGUGCUGGAAUUAUAGGCAUGAGCCACCGCGCCCAGCAAAGAACUUCUAACCUUCAUAACCUGACAGGUGUUCUCCUCGAGGCCAGGGUCUCUCUUUCUGUCCUUUCACGAUGCUCUGCAUCCCUUGGAUGUGCCAGUUUCUGGGGGAAGAGUAGUCCUUUGUUACAUGCAUGAGUCAGUGAACAGGGAAUGGGUGAAUGACAUUUGUGGGUAGGUUAUUUCUAGAAGUUAGGUGGGCAGCUUGGAAGGCAGAUGCACUUCUACAGACUAUUCCUUGGGGCCACACGUAGGUUCUUGAAUCCCGAAUGGAAAGGGGAGAUUGAUAACUGGUGUGUUUAUGUUCUUACAAGUCUUCUGCCUUUUAAAAUCCAGUCCCAGGACAUCAAAGCUCUGCAGAAAGAACUCGAGCAAUUUGCCAAGCUCCUGAAGCAGAAGAGGAUCACCCUGGGAUAUACACAGGCCGAUGUGGGGCUCACCCUGGGGGUUCUAUUUGGGAAGGUAUUCAGCCAAACGACCAUCUGCCGCUUUGAGGCUCUGCAGCUUAGCUUCAAGAACAUGUGUAAGCUGCGGCCCUUGCUGCAGAAGUGGGUGGAGGAAGCUGACAACAAUGAAAAUCUUCAGGAGAUAUGCAAAGCAGAAACCCUCGUGCAGGCCCGAAAGAGAAAGCGAACCAGUAUCGAGAACCGAGUGAGAGGCAACCUGGAGAAUUUGUUCCUGCAGUGCCCGAAACCCACACUGCAGCAGAUCAGCCACAUCGCCCAGCAGCUUGGGCUCGAGAAGGAUGUGGUCCGAGUGUGGUUCUGUAACCGGCGCCAGAAGGGCAAGCGAUCAAGCAGCGACUAUGCACAACGAGAGGAUUUUGAGGCUGCUGGGUCUCCUUUCUCAGGGGGACCAGUGUCCUUUCCUCUGGCCCCAGGGCCCCAUUUUGGUACCCCAGGCUAUGGGAGCCCUCACUUCACUGCACUGUACUCCUCGGUCCCUUUCCCUGAGGGGGAAGCCUUUCCCCCUGUCUCUGUCACCACUCUGGGCUCUCCCAUGCAUUCAAACUGAGGUGCCUGCCCUUCUAGGAAUGGGGGACAGGGGGAGGGGAGGAGCUAGGGAAAGAAAACCUGGAGUUUGUGCCAGGGUUUUUGGGAUUAAGUUCUUCAUUCACUAAGGAAGGAAUUGGGAACACAAAGGGUGGGGGCAGGGGAGUUUGGGGCAACUGGUUGGAGGGAAGGUGAAGUUCAAUGAUGCUCUUGAUUUUAAUCCCACAUCAUGUAUCACUUUUUUCUUAAAUAAAGAAGCUUGGGACACAGUAGAUAGACACACUUA